CUGCACAAACCAACCACACAGAGAAGGCCAGUAUAGAUUCGGAAACAGAAAACAAAAGCAGGAAAAGUGACCUUAGCCCGGAUUCUGCCAUCCCCGGAAGGCUUAUUCCUCCUAUGGGCAAAGGAGCAAAGGGAGCCAGAAGAUGAAAGCGAGCUCAGGGAGGUGCGGGCUGGUGCGGUGGCUGCAGGUACUGUUGCCCUUCCUGUUGUCUUUGUUCCCCGGGGCUCUCCCAGUCCAGAUCCGCUAUUCAAUUCCAGAGGAGCUGGCCAAAAACUCGGUCGUAGGAAACCUCGCCAAGGAUCUGGGGCUCAGCGUCCGGGACUUGCCAGCCCGGAAGCUGCGGGUUAGCGCGGAGAAGGAAUAUUUCACAGUAAACCCAGAAAGCGGAGACUUACUUGUGAGUGACAGAAUAGACCGAGAACAGAUAUGCGGGAAGCAGCCUCUGUGUGUUCUGGAUUUCGAUACUGUCGCUGAAAAUCCACUAAAUAUUUUCUACAUAGCAGUAAUUGUGCAGGAUAUAAAUGAUAAUACCCCGCUAUUCAAACAGACUAAGAUUAAUUUAAAAAUUGGCGAAUCCACUAAGCCAGGUACAACAUUUCCACUUGACCCAGCCCUGGAUUCAGAUGUUGGUCCUAACUCACUACAAAGAUACCACCUUAAUGACAACGAGUACUUUGAUCUCGCUGAGAAACAGACUCCAGAUGGUCGUAAAUAUCCUGAGUUGAUUCUAAAACACUCUCUGGACAGAGAAGAGCACAGUUUACAUCAAUUGGUCCUCACAGCUGUGGAUGGCGGAGACCCACCUCAAAGUGGCACGACCCAAAUCCGAAUCAAAGUCACGGAUGCCAACGAUAACCCUCCAGUGUUCAGCCAGGACGUGUACAGGGUCACCCUGAGGGAGGACGUGCCGCCGGGCUUCUUUGUGCUUCAAGUGACAGCCACCGACCGGGAUGAAGGCAUAAACGCAGAGAUCACCUACUCCUUUCAUAAUGUGGACGAACAAGUGAAACACUUUUUCAACUUAAAUGAAAAAACAGGAGAAAUCACGACAAAGGAUGAUUUGGAUUUUGAGAUUGCAAGUAGUUACACUCUGAGUAUCGAAGCAAAAGAUCCUGGAGAUCUAGCAGCCCACUGCAGUAUCCAAGUUGAAAUUCUUGAUGACAACGAUUGUGCACCUGAAGUUAUUGUGACUUCAGUAUCUACUCCCCUACCGGAGGAUUCGCCACCAGGAACAGUGAUCGCCUUGAUAAAAACGAGAGACAGAGACUCUGGAGAAAAUGGAGAAGUUUACUGCCAAGUGUUGGGAAAUGCCAAGUUUAUUUUGAAAUCUUCCUCAAAGAACUAUUACAAACUAGUGACAGACGGCGCUCUGGACCGGGAGGAGAUCCCAGAAUACAAUCUCACCAUCACAGCCACCGACGGGGGCAAGCCGCCCCUCUCCUCCAGCAUAAUUGUCACCCUGCACAUCUCCGACGUCAACGAUAAUGCCCCAGUUUUCCAACAGACUUCCUACAUGGUUCACGUGGCAGAGAACAAUCCUCCUGGCGCCUCUAUCGCUCAAAUCAGUGCCUCUGACCCUGACUUGGGCCCCAGUGGCCAAGUUUCCUACUCCAUCGUAGCGAGCGACCUGAAGCCGCGGGAGAUUUUAUCCUACGUGUCCGUGAGCGCGCAGAGCGGGGUGGUGUUCGCGCAGCGCGCCUUCGAUCAUGAGCAGCUGCGCGCCUUCGAGCUCACACUGCAGGCCCGCGACCAGGGCUCGCCCGCGCUCAGCGCCAACGUGAGCCUGCGCGUGUUAGUGGGCGACCUCAAUGACAAUGCGCCACGGGUGCUGUACCCCGCGCUGGGGCCUGAUGGCUCCGCCCUCUUCGAUAUGGUGCCACGCGCCGCAGAGCCCGGCUACCUGGUGACCAAGGUGGUGGCGGUGGACGCAGACUCAGGACACAACGCUUGGCUGUCCUACCACGUGCUGCAGGCCAGCGAGCCCGGGCUCUUCAGCCUGGGGUUGCGCACGGGUGAGGUGCGCACAGCGCGUGCCUUGGGCGACAGGGACGCGGCCCGCCAGCGCCUGCUGGUCGCUGUGCGUGAUGGAGGACAGCCGCCACUCUCCGCUACGGCCACGCUGCACCUAAUCUUCGCGGAUAGCCUGCAAGAGGUAUUGCCAGACCUCAGCGACCGCCGGGAGCCCUCUGACCCCCAGGCAAAACUGCAGUUUUACCUGGUUGUGGCCUUGGCCUUGAUCUCAGUGCUCUUCUUCCUCGCGGUGAUUCUGGCAAUCUCCCUGCGCCUGCGACUCUCUUCCAGGUCAGAUGCUUGGGACUGUUUUCAGCCUGGUCUCAGCUCCAAGCCUGGACCUGGGGUUCUCCCCAAUUACAGUGAGGGUACAUUGCCCUAUUCCUACAACCUGUGUGUUGCCUCACAAUCAGCCAAGACAGAGUUCAAUUUUCUGAACAUAACCCCGGAAUUGGUUCCCGCGCAAGAUCUCGUCUGUGACAAUGCCUCUUGGGAACAAAAUACAAAUCAUGGAGCCGCUGGGGUCCCUUUUGCCUCAGAUACUAUUUUGAAGCAAGCCCCGCCCAACACGGACUGGCGUUUCUCUCAGGCCCAGAGACCCGGCACCAGCGGCUCCCAAAAUGGCGAUGACACCGGCACCUGGCCCAACAACCAGUUUGACACAGAGAUGCUGCAAGCCAUGAUCUUGGCGUCCGCCAGUGAAGCUGCUGAUGGGAGCUCCACCCUGGGAGGGGGUGCCGGCACCAUGGGAUUGAGCGCCCGCUACGGACCCCAGUUCACCCUGCAGCACGUGCCCGACUACCGCCAGAAUGUCUACAUCCCAGGCAGCAAUGCCACACUGACCAACGCAGCUGGCAAGCGGGAUGGCAAGGCCCCAGCAGGUGGCAAUGGCAACAAGAAGAAGUCGGGCAAGAAGGAGAAGAAGUAACAUGGAGGCCAGGCCAAGAGCCACAGGGCGGCCUCUCCCCAACCAGCCCAGCUUCUCCUUACCUGCACCCAGGCCUCAGAGUUUCAGGGCUAACCCCCAGAAUACUGGUAGGGGCCAAGGCCAUGCUCCCCUUGGGAAACAGAAACAAGUGCCCAGUCAGCACCUACCCCUUCCCCCCCAGGGGGUUGAAUAUGCAAAAGCAGUUCCGCUGGGAACCCCCAUCCAAUCAACUGCUGUACCCAUGGGGGUAGUGGGGUUACUGUAGACACCAAGAACCAUUUGCCACACCCCGUUUAGUUACAGCUGAACUCCUCCAUCUUCCAAAUCAAUCAGGCCCAUCCAUCCCAUGCCUCCCUCCUCCCCACCCCACUCCAACAGUUCCUCUUUCCCGAGUAAGGUGGUUGGGGUGUUGAAGUACCAAGUAACCUACAAGCCUCCUAGUUCUGAAAAGUUGGAAGGGCAUCAUGACCUCUUGGCCUCUCCUUUGAUUCUCAAUCUUCCCCCAAAGCAUGGUUUGGUGCCAGCCCCUUCACCUCCUUCCAGAGCCCAAGAUCAAUGCUCAAGUUUUGGAGGACAUGAUCACCAUCCCCAUGGUACUGAUGCUUGCUGGAUUUAGGGAGGGCAUUUUGCUACCAAGCCUCUUCCCAACGCCCUGGGGACCAGUCUUCUGUUUUGUUUUUCAUUGUUUGACGUUUCCACUGCAUGCCUUGACUUCCCCCACCUCCUCCUCAAACAAGAGACUCCACUGCAUGUUCCAAGACAGUAUGGGGUGGUAAGAUAAGGAAGGGAAGUGUGUGGAUGUGGAUGGUGGGGGCAUGGACAAAGCUUGACACAUCAAGUUAUCAAGGCCUUGGAGGAGGCUCUGUAUGUCCUCAGGGGACUGACAACAUCCUCCAGAUUCCAGCCAUAAACCAAUAACUAGGCUGGACCCUUCCCACUACAUAAUAGGGCUCAGCCCAGGCAGCCAGCUUUGGGCUGAGCUAACAGGACCAAUGGAUUAAACUGGCAUUUCAGUCCAAGGAAGCUCGAAGCAGGUUUAGGACCAGGUCCCCUUGAGAGGUCAGAGGGGCCUCUGUGGGUGCUGGGUACUCCAGAGGUGCCACUGGUGGAAGGGUCAGCGGAGCCCCAGCAGGAAGGGUGGGCCAGCCAGGCCAUUCUUAGUCCCUGGGUUGGGGAGGCAGGGAGCUAGGGCAGGGACCAAAUGAACAGAAAGUCUCAGCCCAGGAUGGGGCUUCUUCAACAGGGCCCCUGCCCUCCUGAAGCCUCAGUCCUUCACCUUGCCAGGUGCCGUUUCUCUUCCGUGAAGGCCACUGCCCAGGUCCCCAGUGCGCCCCCUAGUGGCCAUAGCCUGGUUAAAGUUCCCCAGUGCCUCCUUGUGCAUAGACCUUCUUCUCCCACCCCCUUCUGCCCCUGGGUCCCCGGCCAUCCAGCGGGGCUGCCAGAGAACCCCAGACCUGCCCUUACAGUAGUGUAGCGCCCCCUCCCUCUUUCGGCUGGUGUAGAAUAGCCAGUAGUGUAGUGCGGUGUGCUUUUACGUGAUGGCGGGUGGGCAGCGGGCGGCGGGCUCCGCGCAGCCGUCUGUCCUUGAUCUGCCCGCGGCGGCCCGUGUUGUGUUUUGUGCUGUGUCCACGCGCUAAGGCGACCCCCUCCCCCGUACUGACUUCUCCUAUAAGCGCUUCUCUUCGCAUAGUCACGUAGCUCCCACCCCACCCUCUUCCUGUGUCUCACGCAAGUUUUAUACUCUAAUAUUUAUAUGGCUUUUUUUCUUCGACAAAAAAAUAAUAAAACGUUUCUUCUGAAAA